AGUUUGUUCCUGCUGCCAGGCUCCACUGAGGGGAACGGGGACCUGUCUGAAGAGAAGAUGCCCCUGCUGACACUCUACCUGCUCCUCUUCUGGCUCUCAGAACCACUAGAAAUCAUUAGGACCACCAGGACAGCCUCUCCACAGCCAUCUGAUGUGGCUGCCUCAGCUCGACCUCAUGAGGGUCAUCAGUGCUAAGAGUCAAGGCUACUCCAUUGUCACUCAAAUCACCGGUCCAACAACAGUGAAUGGCUUGGAGCGGGGCUCCUUGACCGUGCAGUGUGUUUACAGAUCAGGCUGGGAGACCUACUUGAAGUGGUGGUGUCGAGGAGCUAUUUGGCGUGACUGCAAGAUCCUUGUUAAAACCAGUGGGUCAGAGCAGGAGGUGAAGAGGGACCGGGUGUCCAUCAAGGACAAUCAGAAAAACCGCACGUUCACUGUGACCAUGGAGGAUCUCAUGAAAACUGAUGCUGACACUUACUGGUGUGGAAUUGAGAAAACUGGAAAUGACCUUGGGGUCACAGUUCAAGUGACCAUUGACCCAGCAUCAACUACAGCGUCGACUCCUGCCCCCACCACGCCUACCUCCACUACGUUUACAGCACCAGUCACCCAAGAAGAAACUAGCAGCUCCCCAACUCUGACCGGCCACCACUUGGACAACAGGAUCCCCAGGAGUGAGGGUUCCCAGGCUGCAAACUACAGACCUGCAGCUCAUCAGGGGACGCUUGCCAUUGUUUCUAGGCACAAGCUCCUGAAGCUCAGUGUCCUCCUGCCCCUCAUCUUCACCAUAUUGCUGCUGCUUUUGGUGGCCGCCUCACUCUUGGCUUGGAGGAUGAUGAAGUACCAGCAGAAAGCAGCCGGGAUGUCCCCAGAGCAGGUACUGCAGCCCCUGGAGGGCGACCUCUGCUAUGCAGACCUGACCCUGCAGCUGGCCGGAACCUCCCCGCAAAAGGCUACCACGAAGCUUUCCUCUGCCCAGGUUGACCAGGUGGAAGUGGAAUAUGUCACCAUGGCUUCCUUGCCGAAGGAGGACAUUUCCUAUGCAUCUCUGACCUUGGGUGCUGAGGAUCAGGAACCGACCUACUGCAACAUGGGCCACCUCAGUAGCCACCUCCCCGGCAGGGGCCCUGAGGAGCCCACGGAAUACAGCACCAUCAGCAGGCCUUAGCCUGCACUCCAGGCUCCUUCUUGGACCCCAGGCUGUGAGCACACUCCUGCCUCAUCGACCGUCUGCCCCCUGCUCCCCUCAUCAGGACCAACCCGGGGACUGGUGCCUCUGCCUGAUCAGCCAGCAUUGCCCCUAGCUCUGGGUUGGGCUUGGGGCCAAGUCUCAGGGGGCUUCUAGGAGUUGGGGUUUUCUAAACGUCCCCUCCUCUCCUACAUAGUUGAGGAGGGGGCUAGGGAUAUGCUCUGGGGCUUUCAUGGGAAUGAUGAAGAUGAUAAUGAGAAAAAUGUUAUCAUUAUUAUCAUGAAGUACCAUUAUCGUAAUACAAUGAACCUUUAUUUAUUGCCUACCACAUGUUAUGGGCUGAAUAAUGGCCCCCAAAGAUAUCUGUGUCCUAAUCCUCAGAACCUGUGACUGUUACCUUCUGUGGCAGAAAGGGACAGUGCAGAUGUAUGUAAGUUAAGGACUUUGAGAUAGAGAGGUUAUUCUUGCUGAUUCAGGUGGGCCCAAAAUAUCACCACAAGGGUCCUCAUAAGAAAGAGGCCAGAAGGUCAAAGAGGUAGAGACAAAGUGAUGAUGGAAGUGGACGUGGGUGUGACGUGAGCAGGGGCCAUGAAUGCCGCAGCCUUCAGAUGCCAGAAAGGGAAAGGAAUGGAUUCCCCUGCCUGGAGCCUCCAAAAGAAACCAGCCCUGCCCACGCCUUGACUUGAGCCCAUUGAAACUGAUCUUGAGCUCCUGGCCUCCAGAAUUGCAGGAGAAUAAAUUUGUGUUGUUUUUAAUGA